GUGUCUAGCGGGAUCGCUUGCUUGGUAACCCGGAGGGAGAGAUUGGAAACCGCGGAGUUUCCUUUGGGAGGCUGCGGCCAGCCGGGGCUGACUUGUUAUGUUGGGCUCCGGAGGCCGUUAAGAGCCGAGAGAGACAUGAGGUGUCUCUGAAGCCCGGUCGCCUGGGCCAUGAAGAAGAUUUUUAGUAAGAAGGGCGAGUCGCCCUUGGGCUCCUUCGCGCGGCGGCAGAGGAGCAGCGCGGGAGGCGGGGGCGAGCCGGGGGAGGGCGCCUACUCGCAGCCCGGCUACCACGUCCGAGACCGAGAUCUCGGCAAGAUCCACAAAGCUGCCAGCGCGGGUAAUGUGGCGAAAGUGCAGCAGAUCCUUUUGCUCAGGAAGAAUGGCUUGAACGAUAGAGACAAGAUGAACAGGACGGCUCUACAUUUGGCCUGUGCCAAUGGUCAUCCAGAAGUAGUAACUCUCCUGGUGGACAGAAAAUGCCAGCUCAAUGUCUGUGACAACGAAAACAGGACAGCUCUGAUGAAGGCUGUACAAUGCCAGGAAGAGAAAUGUGCAACUAUUCUGCUAGAACAUGGUGCUGAUCCAAAUCUUGCGGAUGUCCAUGGCAACACUGCUCUUCACUAUGCUGUCUAUAAUGAGGACAUAUCAGUAGCAACAAAGCUGCUUUUGUAUGAUGCAAAUAUUGAAGCAAAAAACAAGGAUGACCUCACACCACUUUUACUUGCAGUAAGUGGAAAAAAGCAGCAAAUGGUGGAAUUUUUAAUAAAGAAAAAAGCAAAUGUAAAUGCAGUAGAUAAGUUGGAAAGCAGUCACCAACUAAUUUCAGAAUAUAAAGAAGAAAGGAUACCUAAACAUUCUUCUCAAAAUAGUAAUUCAGUGGAUGAAAGCUCUGAAGACUCCUUAAGCAGGCUUUCUGGCAAACCGGGUGUUGAUGAUUCAUGGCCUACCUCAGAUGACGAAGACCUCAAUUUUGAUACUAAGAAUGUCCCAAAACCAAGCUUAGCAAAGCUAAUGACUGCUUCUCAGCAAUCCAGGAAAAAUUUAGAAGCAACAUAUGGCACUGUGAGAACAGGAAAUAGAACUUUGUUUGAGGAUAGAGAUUCCGAUAGUCAAGAUGAAGUUGUGGUUGAAAGCCUUCCUACAACAUCAAUCAAAGUCCAGUGCUUUUCUCAUCCUACCUAUCAAUCACCUGACCUUCUUCCAAAACCUUCCCACAAGUCGUUAGCAAACCCUGGUCUUAUGAAGGAAGAACCAACAAAGCCAGGCAUUGCAAAAAAAGAAAAUGGUAUUGAUAUUAUUGAAAGUGCUCCACUAGAGCAAACAAAUAAUGACAAUUUGACUUAUGUUGAUGAAGUGCACAAAAAUAAUAGAAGUGAUAUGAUGUCCGCAUUAGGAUUAGGACAAGAGGAAGAUAUAGAAUCACCUUGGGAUUCUGAGAGUAUCUCUGAGAAUUUUCCACAGAAGUAUGUUGAUCCUUUAGCUGGGGCUGCAGACGGAAAAGAAAAAAAUAUAGGAAAUGAACAAGCAGAAGAUGUGUUUUAUAUACCUUCUUGCAUGAGUGGAUCAAGAAACUUUAAGAUGGCUAAACUAGAGGAUACAAGAAAUCAUGCUCACAUUGAGUCUCCUGAGAGAUAUCUUCACUUGAAGCCUACCAUUGAAAUGAAAGAUUCUGUUCCAAAUAAAGCAGGAGGAAUGAAGGAUGUACAAACAUCCAAAGCAGCUGAACAUGACUUAGAAGUAGCAUCAGAAGAAGAGCAAGAAAGGGAAGGGAGUGAAAAUAACCAGCCACAGGAUAAAGUUAUUUUAAAAACAUGCACCCUGACAGAAAAGACAUCUGAAAAACAAAACAAGCAAAUUAAUCGUCCACUUUCAUGUCUGCAAAAGAUGUCUCAAGAACCAGAACUGAAUAAGGAGUGUGAUAGAGAGGAUGUAUCUGUAUAUUCAGGACUUCCUUGUGUGCAAAAUGAUGAAGAAAUGUGGACCAAACAAGGCAAAUUAGAGUGGAAAAAUAACUUAAAACUCAUCACAAAUGAGUUAAAGCAGAGCUGUGGUGAAACUUGUGAAAAAUACAAAAUUACUGCUUCUCCUGGGGAAGAGUCACUACAUGAUAACUCUAAAGGAGGCACAAACUUAAAGGAAAUACCUUCUUCUUUGACAAAUAAUAUACUUGAUUGCGAUGAAAAAGAUUCUCCUGUCUCUGUACUAUUCCAGGCAUUGCCUGAACAAAAAGUACUCAGUCUCGAAAAUGGCUUUUCAUUUCCUUCAUACUCUGGGUCCCCAGAAUAUGCUUGCCAGUCAUCUUCUAAGCCUUAUUUAAAUGAAAAUAAAUUAGGCCAUGAAAAUGUUAACAAACCAGACACUGAACAUGUUUUUAACACAGAUGAGAAUUUUUAUAAUGAUACAGAAAAUAAAAAAGUAAGGAACCCAGAAGUAGUUACAGGUGUAAUGAAAGAAGAGUUUGAUAAGACAAAAAAUAUGAACCGAAAUACCACUAACUGGAAAUUAGACAUCAGACGUGUGCCUCAGUAUAGUGAUCCAAAAAGACCUUUUGAUUUGAUCUGCUCCAAAGAAAUGAAUCAUAUGUUUCACAUAAAAAGGCAUAGUAUUUCUGCUGGUACAGACGCUUACAAGAAAACAAAACCAAUACAGAACUUGUUCCAGAAGCCAUUAUAUGAUCAUUGCAGUGCUAAUAACUAUAAAAGCAUGGAACCUGAAUUAGAAAAUGUGAGGUCUUCUCCACCACGUGGUGACAGAACAUCAAAAGUAUCUCUAAAAGAAGAAUUACAGCAAGAUAUGCAAAGGUUUAAAAAUGAGAUAGGCAUGUUAAAAGUAGAGUUCCAGGCUUUGGAGAAAGAAAAAGUCCAACUUCAAAAAGAGGUUGAAGAAGAAAGGAAAAAACACAGAAAUAAUGAAAUGGAAGUAUCAGCAAACAUACAUGAUGGUGCUACUGAUGAUGCUGAAGAUGAUGAUGAUGAUGAUGGAUUAAUUCAAAAAAGAAAGAGUGGAGAAACUGAUCAUCAGCAAUUUCCCAGGAAGGAAAAUAAAGAGUAUGCUAGUAGUGGUCCUGCCUUGCAAAUGAAGGAAGUAAAGAGCACUGAAAAAGAAAAACGGACCUCGAAAGAAUCUGUGAAUUCACCAGUGUUUGGGAAGGCCAGUUUACUAACUGGUGGCCUGCUACAAGUGGAUGAUGACAGCAGUUUAAGUGAAAUAGAUGAGGAUGAAGGAAGGCCUACUAAGAAAACAUCUAAUGAAAAGAACAAGGUCAAAAACCAAAUACAGUCUAUGGAUGAUGUUGAUGACUUAACUCAGUCAUCUGAAACAGCCUCAGAGGAUUGUGAGCUACCCCACUCUAGUUACAAGAAUUUUAUGUUGCUCAUUGAACAACUUGGAAUGGAGUGUAAAGAUUCUGUUAGCCUAUUGAAAAUCCAGGAUGCAGCUCUUUCAUGUGAAAGAUUAUUAGAACUUAAAAAAAAUCACUGUGAACUACUUACAGUAAAAAUUAAAAAAAUGGAAGACAAGGUUAAUGUACUACAAAGGGAGCUAUCUGAAACAAAAGAAAUAAAAUCACAGUUAGAGCAUCAAAAAGUUGAAUGGGAACGAGAACUGUGCUCUUUGAGAUUUAGCUUAAACCAAGAAGAAGAGAAGAGAAGAAAUGCUGAUACGUUGUAUGAAAAAAUUAGGGAACAGUUAAGAAGAAAAGAAGAGCAAUAUAGGAAAGAAGUUGAAGUGAAACAACAGCUUGAACUGAGUCUCCAAACACUGGAGAUGGAAUUGAGGACUGUAAAAAGUAAUUUGAAUCAGGUCGUUCAAGAGCGAAAUGACGCUCAGAGGCAACUUUCUCGAGAACAGAAUGCCAGAAUGUUACAAGAUGGAAUUCUGACCAAUCACCUUUCCAAACAAAAGGAGAUUGAAAUGGCUCAAAAGAAAAUGAAUUCUGAGAAUUCUCAUAGUCAUGAAGAAGAAAAAGACCUAUCGCAUAAAAAUAGCAUGUUGCAGGAAGAAAUUGCUAUGCUAAGACUAGAAAUAGACACAAUAAAAAAUCAAAACCAGGAAAAAGAAAAGAAAUGUUUUGAGGACCUUAAAAUUGUAAAAGAAAAGAAUGAAGACCUUCAGAAGACUAUAAAACAGAAUGAGGAAACAUUAACACAAACAAUAUCCCAGUAUAAUGGACGGCUUAGUGUUCUGACAGCUGAGAAUGCAAUGCUAAAUUCUAAACUGGAGAAUGAAAAGCAAAGCAAGGAAAGACUGGAAGCAGAAGUUGAAUCAUACCAUUCUAGAUUGGCUGCUGCUAUACAUGAUCGUGAUCAAAGUGAGACAUCAAAAAGAGAACUAGAACUUGCUUUCCAGAGAGCAAGAGAUGAAUGUUCUCGUUUACAGGACAAAAUGAAUUUUGAUGUGUCUAACCUAAAAGAUAACAAUGAGAUUCUUUCUCAACAACUAUUUAAAACUGAAAGUAAACUCAAUAGCCUAGAAAUUGAGUUCCAUCACACGAGAGAUGCCCUCAGAGAAAAGACUUUGGGUUUAGAACGGGUACAAAAGGACCUAAGCCAAACACAGUGUCAAAUGAAGGAAAUGGAACAAAAGUAUCAAAAUGAACAAGUUAAAGUGAAUAAAUACAUUGGAAAGCAGGAGUCUGUAGAGGAGAGAUUGUCUCAACUACAAAGUGAGAAUAUGUUGCUUCGACAACAACUGGAUGAUGCCCACAACAAGGCUGACAAUAAAGAGAAGACAGUGAUUAAUAUCCAAGACCAGUUUCAUGCUAUUGUGCAAAAACUUCAAGCUGAGAGUGAAAAGCAAAGUCUUCUGCUAGAAGAAAGAAAUAAGGAGUUAAUCAGUGAAUGUAAUCACUUAAAAGAAAGACAGUAUCAAUAUGAAAAUGAAAAGGCAGAAAGAGAAGUUGUUGUGAGACAACUUCAACAAGAACUAGCUGAUACCCUAAAAAAACAAUCUAUGUCAGAGGCUUCACUGGAGGUUACGUCACGUUAUCGUAUUAAUUUAGAAGAUGAGACACAGGAUUUAAAGAAGAAAUUAGGUCAAAUCAGAAAUCAAUUGCAAGAAGCACAGGAUCGACAUACAGAAGCUGUCAGAUGUGCUGAGAAGAUGCAAGAUCACAAGCAAAAGCUUGAAAAAGAUAAUGCCAAGUUAAAAGUUACAGUCAAAAAGCAAAUGGACAAAAUUGAGGAGCUUCAGAAAAACCUGUUAAAUGCAAAUUUGUCUGAAGAUGAAAAGGAACAAUUAAAGAAACUUAUGGAAUUAAAACAGUCACUGGAAUGUAAUUUGGAUCAAGAAAUGAAGAAAAAUGUUGAAUUAGAAAGAGAGAUAACUGGAUUUAAGAACCUCUUAAAAAUGACAAGAAAGAAGUUAAAUGAAUAUGAAAAUGGAGAAUUUAGUUUCCAUGGAGAUUUAAAAACUAGUCAAUUUGAAAUGGAUAUUCAGAUUAAUAAGCUAAAACAUAAGAUUGAUGAUCUUACAGCAGAACUGGAGACUGCAGGUUCAAAAUGUCUACAUCUGGAUACAAAGAACCAAAUUCUUCAAGAGGAGUUGUUAUCUAUGAAAACAGUACAAAAGAAAUGUGAAAAACUACAGAAGAAUAAAAAGAAGUUGGAACAAGAAGUGAUCAACCUGAGAAGUCAUAUAGAAAGGAAUAUGGUAGAACUUGGUCAAGUCAAACAGUAUAAACAGGAGAUUGAAGAAAGAGCAAGACAGGAAAUAGCAGAAAAAUUAAAAGAAGUCAAUCUAUUUUUACAGGCACAAGCAGCAUCUCAAGAAAACUUAGAGCAGUUUAGAGAGAAUAAUUUUGCUUCAAUGAAAAGUCAGAUGGAACUCAGAAUUAAAGAUCUGGAAUCUGAACUCUCCAAAAUAAAAACUUCUCAAGAAGACUUUAAUAAAACCGAACUGGAAAAAUAUAAGCAACUCUAUCUAGAAGAAUUAAAAGUUAGAAAAUCUUUGUCAAGUAAACUAACCAAAACUAAUGAGAGGCUAGCAGAGGUCAACACCAAACUUCUUGUGGAAAAACAGCAGAGCAGAUCUUUGUUCACCACUCUCACUACCAGGCCAGUCAUGGAGCCACCUUGUGUGGGAAAUCUUAAUAAUAGUUUAGAUCUCAACAGAAAACUUAUUCCAAGAGAAAACUUAGUGAUCUCUACCUCAAAUCCACGGGCUUCAAAUAAUAGCAUGGAGAACUACUUGAGCAAGAUGCAGCAGGAGUUGGAAAAAAAUAUAACUAGAGAACUCAAAGAAGGUACAUCCCCAGCUUACUCCGACCUCUCUGAACUUCCUGGACCAGAUCUGUUUCCUCUGCCUGCAUGCUCUAGCCUACCAUCUUCCUCUCCUUGUCUGCUACUCACUCAACAGAAGGCAACAGGGUGGUCUACUUCUACAACUCCGUCUCCUGAUGAUUUCACAACAGUCUCCCUGGCAGCCUUUCAUCUGGAAGAAGUGGAAAAGGGGGAACCUGUAGGAACAUCUCUCAUGAUCACACCAUAUAGGGAAUGACCAGUAACAGCUGCCAAUCAGAUUAAUCAAACAUGGAAAAAAAAGAUGAGGUUGCAAUUGGGGGAAUAGGAUGCAAUUUUCCAGGAGAUUGAAUGAAUUUGACAAUAACUUGUUUGGAAUUAGUGACUUGGAAGCUGAAUGUCUGGAUCCUCAGCAGAAAUUGCUUCUGGAAUGCACCUAUGGAGCCCUGGAGAGUGCUGGAGUCCCUGCCAAGGAGGUGGCUGGUUCCAGGACAGGAGUCUUCAUUGAGUCUAAACGGGAUCUGGAUCCCUAAGGAACUUCUUGGAGCCAAUUGAAAUCUGAGAUUUCCUACUCCCAGAUGUCUUUUGAAAUUAACUUCGGAUCCAGGGCAGGUACCCUCUAGGUAUUAUGAAUCAAGACUAUGAAUUUAUGUCCCGUAGAACUCCAAGAAUGCAAACCACCGUAAUGCCACUGGAUCUGCAAUGAGCAUAGCUGCUAACAGGAUUUCUUAUGUGUUUAACCUAACUGGCCCCUCUUUUGCUAUAGAUUCUGCAUGCUCAUCAUCUUUUGUUGCACUGUACUACGCCUUCCUUGCAAUUAAACAAGCAUAUUUUCCUUGUAAGACCACUUUAAGAUGAAACUGAGUAAGUAUCAAAGUGUGAUUUCUAAGAAUGACAUCUCUAAAUAUUUGAAUUUUAAACACAGAUAGUCAUUUAUAAUUAGACUAAUAAUAUUAACUUUAAAAAAUUAUUUUAAACAAAUAUUUUAGUGAGUUAAGUAUUUGUGUUAUGAAAAAAUAUUGCCUAACCUUUGAAACUGCUACAAGACGUACUCUUGAUUUGAAAGGAGUUGGGAAGGAGAUUGAAAAAAAUACAGUUUCCACUUUAUGAACAUAAUUUUCUUCCACAGGAUCAACAGGAACCACAGCUGAUAAAAUAAAACAGCCUUCUUAAUGUUCUCACUUGUUGCAUACACAGGACUAAUAUCCCUUAGAAAGUGUAUGGUUCUUCAAGAAACUCAAGUCACUAUUUUCUUUAUGCUUUGUUAUUUAAAGGCUACUUUGCCAUUUCAACACGAUCUAGCCAACAUUCAUUUAGGACAGUACAUGGAACUGUUCAAGAGGCUAGGAAAUGGAAAAAGUUUAAUACAGGAAGACACAUACCCUGUCUUCAAAGAUCUUCUCACUCAUGGAAGGCAAAUUGGAUUGGAACAUAUUUAUACACAUAUAUAUAUAUACACACACAUAUAUACACAUAUAUGUACAUAUAUACAUACACACAUAUAUAUAUAUUUUUUUUUUUGAGAUGGAGUUUCUCUCUUGUUGCACAGGCUAGAGUGCAAUGGUGCGAUCUCGGCUCACUGCAACCUCCGCCUCCUAGGUUCAAGCCAUUAUCCUGCCUCAGCCUCCCAAGUAGCUGGGAUUACAGGCAUGUGCCACCACGACCGGCUAAUUUUGUACUUUUAGUAGAGAUGGGGUUUCACCAUGUUGGUCAGGCUGGUCUCAAACUCCUGACCUCAGGUGAUCUGCUCACCUCGGCCUCCCAAAGUGCUGGGAUUAUGGGCAUGAGCUACUGCGCCCAACCCCAAAAUAUAUAUUUUUAAAUGGAGGUGAGCUGCAUUAUAGAAUUACAAGUAUAGUACUAGUUAAUUCAAUGGAACCAAAAUCCAUCAGGCACACAAUCACAUGCAUUCUGCCCUUUGGAAACACAAUUAGCUAAAGGAAACAGAUGGACAAGAGACAUAAAUAACUUUAAGACCAGGCAAUACAUGGCUUACUAGAUGCACAAAACUGCUAUAGAUCCCGCAUUUGAUAGCUGCCCGCCCACAAAGCUAAAAGUUUAGAAAUUGCCUCUGCAGAGACAAACUAUGUUUCAUAAAGUCCAUACACUAAAACACAUGUACCAUAUUUUAAAAGCUGUAGAGGAAAAGAAAGCUUUGAACAUGCUUUAGAUUCUCAGAACAUAUCUACUCUUAUUUUAUAAACAAUACCUAAACUCGUAAUCUGUUUUUCCAAUCCAAAGCAAUUAAAACAAAAACAAAUAGAAGAGAGUAGGUGUAUUAAUACAACUAUAAGACUAAGGGACAAGAAAACCUGUUUCUGGAUACAGAUUUAUUGUCAAAGUGUAUCACCAAAUUAUUUAAUAAACAUAAUAGAAAUCCAAUUAAUACGCUAGCAGGAUUUUUUUUUUAAGAAAUAGACAAUCUUAGUGUACAAAUCUGAAAAAAUAAACAGGUAAGUUUUUUUAAGCAAGAGAAACAAGUUUGCUUAUGUUAAAAGAAUACAAUAACUAAAAAUAUUACUGUCUUAAAAAUAGAUGCAAAGAUCAAUGGAUCUCAAUAAAAAGCACAGAAACAACCCAAAGCUAUAAAAGAAUUUCCUGUAUAGUGAAAAUGACAUUUCAAAUCACUGGAGAAAGGUAGCAUUAGGACAAUUUGCUCCCUGUCUGGAGUAAUGCCAAUUUAUUCCACCCAGGCUUAAGUGAAUUAAAUAUCAGUUACAACAGCAAUUUUCUAACUUCCUGAAAUGAAUAAUAAAAAUUGGCUAAUAUGGGCCACAUUUCACCCUUUAUAUGUCCACUUAAGACCAUGAUGUAUUACAAGGUAGCAUCCUGGGGGAAUAACUGUGUAGUCAAUCAAAAAGUGGCAGAUUUUAACAUUCACGCCAGAAAACCAGACAAUAUAAGUGAAAGAACCAACAGUGUAUUUUCUUGUUUUGUAGGAGAGCCUCUGUGUGGAAUUAACUAGAUUAUAUGAUUGACUCAAUCUCCCUUAUGAUGCUCUCACAUUGGUAGGGCAGGAGCAGCAUAUCACGUUCCAUUAGUAGUUAUAAUUUUGUACUGCUUGAUGCACGUCCCAGCAAGAUAGCUGCUGGGCAAUACAUGUGAUCACCAGCCAUGGAACAAAAAAGGCUAUUUCAGGCAUAUUAAACCCUCACCCAUGUGAUGCUUUAACAAGCUAAUAAGUCAUAGACUAAAAACCCCAGAGAAAAUUCCAAAAGCAUACUAACCCCUUCUCUUAAGAUCUCAGGAAAAUCAGUACUGGCAAAAUUAAAUUCUUUAGAAUUCAGUGUUGCAUAAGACUAUGAAAUUCACAAAAACUAACAACAAAAAUAAAGAUUAGUGAAACUAACCUUUCACUGCAAAUGUUUGAACCUUUUCUCCCAAUAAAUGUGCUUACCAGAGUAAGAUAAUUUGGAUAAUUCAUUGAUCAUUUAUCUAGUAACAUCAGGAUGAGAUGUUUCACACAGUACUGUAAACCAAGACACAGUAAUACAUAGGAUUAUUUAUUUAUUUAUUUGGAGACAGUGUCCCACUCUUUCAUCCACACUGGAGAGCAGUGGCACGAUCGCAACUCACUGCAGCCUCGAACUCUCGAACUUCUGGGCUCAAGCAAACAUCCCUGCCUCAGCCUCCUGAGUAGCUAGGGUUACAGGCACACACCACCACGCCUGGCUAAUUUUAUUUUUUGUAGAGACAGGGUCUUGCUUAUGUUGCCUAGGCUGGUCUCGAUAUCCCGGCCUCAAAUGAACCUCCCACCUCAGCCUCCCAAAUUGCUGGGAUUACAGGCAUGACCCACUCUGUCUGGCCUGGUAUUAUAUUUACAAUCUCUUUGGCUAUAAAACCUGGUCUUAUUGUAGAUAUUAUGUUUUAAACAGUAUAAUCAAUAUUAUGUUUUAAACGGUAUAAUCAAUAUUGGAAGAAAAUGUCUUCGAGGGUAGCUAACACUCUGACAUCAAUACAACAGCCUUGGUCACUUUCAGUUACACAUAGGCCAUUUUGAUCCAUCUGUAUUGGCUCUUUUCGUUUGUCUAAGGGCAGCAAAAUAGACCAAAGAUGUCUUCAGACUGCACAAGAGAAGUCUGUUCUUUAGCAGUUACCAGCAUAACUCAGAUAAUGUUUUUAACUUCCUCAACUCAUGCUUGGCCUAGUUGGGUCAAAAGAACUACUUGUGAAUGCCGUAUGUCCAAUUGGUAGGUUACUGUUUUUUCUCAAGAGUUUAGCUAUACAGUAAUGUUGGAAGUCUUGAGGAACUUCAUCUGCUGUCCCUACUUAGCCUUGCAAUACUACAGCAUCUUUGUUUUAUUUUAUUAUUAUUUUUUAAGAGAGAGUCUCGCUUUGUCGCCUAUGCUGGUGUGCAGUGGCGCAAGCUUGGCUAUUGUUCAAUCAGUAUCAGUUUUAUUGGAAAAUCUCAUAGAAGAAAAAAACAAAUAAUUAUUUCAAUAAAUGUCAAAAAGGCUCUUGAUGAAAUUCAACAUCAAGGUGCCCAAAACCUUGAUAAAAGGUGCCCAAAACCUACAGCAAAGGGCAUAUUUAACAAUAAAGCAUGAACAGAAAUGUCAUUUGCAUUCAUAAAACCCAGGAUUUGUUUUAAUCAGUAAUGGCAAGACACACAAACACAGAAAUGACUGUCAUGAGGGAAGUAGUUUAUUUUUCUACUCACAGUUCCCUAGAAGCUGUGGGCACAGCACACCACAAGCAGAAGGACAGGGAAACAUCAAGGUCAGUCAGGAGGCAGCGUCAAUGGGGGAAAACGUGGGAAAGAGGCUUUAUUGCAGUUCCAUGGGACGGGACAAGCAAGUCAGGUCAAUCAGGCUUAGCAUUGGCUAGUUUGAAUAAUUUCAUUGGCUCCUGGAAAGAAGAGGCUGCUAUCUGGCCCUGAAGAAAUUAGGGAAGUAGAAUAGUGGCCAGAAUUGUGAGAGUGAUAAGGAACAUUAAGACUGCAAAAGAGAUAAACAGAGAUAAAGAAGAAUAAAGAGUGAUGAAGAGAUGAGAAAGAAGGGGGUAUAAACUCUGGGUUGGUUGGGUUAUAGUAGGAAAGUCAUGCAUGCAGGCAAGUUGUUUAUUACAUCCAGCAAUUAGCUUAUCCUGAGAGGGGCAGUCCCUCCAGGGUCAACAAGGCCCAAAUGUCAAAGCAUCAAAUUUAGAAAAUAAGAGAUAUGACUAAUACACCGUUAAAGUCAGUAUUAUAAUUAAUAUUAUUCAACAUUAUCCAACAUUAUCCUGGAGUCUCUAGCCAAUGCAUACAACAGCAAAACCACUAAGAUAAACAAAUAUAUGAAUGGAAAAGACAGACUUUUAAAUUCUCAGGCGAUGUAUCUACUUAAAAUUUUAAAACAAAGUCAAACAAUCCAUUAAAAGCUAUUAAGUAUAGAAACUAAAAACUGUCCUGUGUACUAUAUAUCAGUGAAGCUCAUUUAUAAAAUGUAGUAUAAAAGGUGAGUCACAAGAGCAACAAGAACUAAAAUAUUUUUAGAAUUGCUAGAAAAUUUCAAAUCUAUAUAAGGAAAAUUGUAAAUAUUUAUUGCAGGUAUAAAAGAAAACAUCAGGAAAAAAAGAGGCACAGAUCAUCACUGCUCCACCUAAUUUCAAUAACCAUGAUUUAAUUAAAUAACGUAAGUACCCCAACAUGGUUCCAAAUUCAGUUCAACUGUGAGUGAUUACACAAAGUACAAACUUUGUGUGAGCUCUUCAGUCCACAAAUCACAACAUAAAUAACAGAAGCAAUCAUGAUCAGUGACCCAUCAUUUCUUUCAAAGUAUGAGGUUGUCAAUCACUGCAUAUUUGUUACUGAGUUUAUACAGAGAGCAAAGCAUGUCACUGUCUUGCCUCCUUGUCUCCCAGGGAGAAGCCCACAUGACAUUUUACAAAAAUGAAUAACCAAAGAGGGAAGUGGUCAACAAACAUGAAACUGCAAAAAAAAAAAAAAAAAAGAAAAAGAAAAGAAAAGAAAAAAGAAAAGGGAUAAUACAAAGUGAAAAUCAAAUGGAACAUAAAUGUAGUUAUAGAAGAAAUAGUGGCCAUUCACUGAGGCAGUUGUAUUCUUGGUAUUUCAAUUAUUUUUGACAAAUAAAUCAAUUCUGAAUCAGACUGAAGCUCUAUAUUUACAGAAAUACAGGAGGCACAGACACGUGUUGUGUUAGGUUGCUUUUCUGUUGCUAUAAAGAAAUACCUGAGACUGGGUCAUUUAUAAAGAAAAAAGGUUUAACUGGCUCACAGGUCUGCAGGCUUUACUGGAAGCAUGGUGCUGGCAUCUGCUCAGCUUUUGGGGAGGCCUCAGGAGGCUUCCAUUCAUGGGAAAAGGCAAAGUGGGAGCAGGCUUCUCACAUGGAGAGACUGGGAGCAAGAGAGCAAGCAGAGGAGGUGCCACACACUUUUAAACAACAGAUCUCCUGAGAACUCACUCAUUAUCAGUGGGACAGCACCAAGUUAUGAGGAAUCUGUCCCCAUGACCCAAACACCUCCCACAAGACCCCACCUCCAACAUUGGGGAUUACACCUCAACAUGAGUAUAUUAGUACGUUUUCACACUGCUAUAAAGAAACUACCUGAGACUGGAUAAUUUAUAAAGGAAGGUUUAAUUGACUCACAGUUAUGCAUGGCUCUGGAGGCCUCAGGAAACUUACAAUCAUCACAGAGGGUGAAGGAGAAGCAAAGCACAUCUUACAUGGCAGCAGGAGAGAGAGAGAGCAAAGAGGAAAUGCCAGACAAUUAUUAAACUACCAUAUGUCAUGAGAACUCUCUCACUAUCACAAGAACAGCAUGGGAAAACUGCUCCCAUGAUCCAAUCACCUCCCCACAAGUCCCUGCAUCCACACAUGGGGGUCAUAAUUCAAGAUGAGAUCUGGGUGGGGACAUAGAGCCAAACCAUAUCAAUGAGAUUUGGAGGGGACGUCCAAACUGUAUCACAGGUUCAAUAAAUAAUACCAUAGAAUGCAAUCAGAAAAAUGCAGAAUGCUGAAAUACCACAGGAUAAAUAAUCUGGUUUUUUCAAUCAUAACUAAAGGAACCAAUAGAUUGUAAGUGAAAAAAGGUGUAGGUGACAUAAGUAGGUGAUAAACUCAAAGAUAUCAAAGGAAGCUUAAGACAUAUUAUCAUCUAAUUUUAAUGUAUACUCCUUAUUCAGAUCCCAAUUAAAAUAACUAUAAGAGGCUGGGCACGGUGGGUCACACCUGUAAUCCCAGCACUUUGGGAGGUCGAGGAGGGUGGAUCACGAGGUCAGGAGUUCAAGGCCAGCCUGGCCACGAUGGUGAAAGCCCAUCUCUACUAAAAAUACAAAAAUUAGCCAGGCGUGGUGGCAGGCACCUGUAAUCCCAGCUACUUGGGAGGCUGAGGCAGAGAAUUGCUUGAACCCAGAAGGUGGAAACUGCAUUAAGCCGAAAUCUCGCCACUGCACUCCAGCCUGGGCGACAGAGUGAGACACUGGUCAAAAAUAAAUAAAUUAAUAAAUAAAUUAAUUAAUAUAACUAUAAGAUAAUGAUGAUAAUUAUAAGAAAAUAGGAAAAUCUUGAAAACUGAAUAAUGUGAUACAUUAGGAGUUACUACUAAUUUGUCUCAAGGUCAUAUGAUGUCAUGGACUGUUUGUAUUUUAAGUCAUUAAUAUUUAGAGAUGCAAACACAAAUAUUUGUAGAGGAAAUGAAACAAUGUCUGUAUUUUCCAAAAAAAUGAGGACAUGUAUAUCAUACUUCAAUUAAGGCAACAAUGAGGAAUAUGGGGGAAGGGUGUGGAGGUGUAGGUGAAGCAAAAUUGGCAAGGUAUUAAUCACUAGUAAGCUGAUUAAAUGGUAAAUUAGGUUCAUUAAACCAUUAAAAUUUUCUGUACCUUAGUAAAUGUUUGAAAAUUCUAUAAUAGAAUAAAAAACUCUAGGAGCAUAAUAAAACUAAAUACCCACUGAUAUGCCCCAAAGUGCUGAAUUUACAGUAAAUACUAGAUCAGUAUUUAAUAAUGCAUUUUUUUUAGAUGGCGUUUCACUCUUGUUGCCCAGGCUGGAGUGCAAUGGUGAGAUUUCGGCUCACUGCAACCUCCGCCUCCCGGGUUCAAGCGAUUCUCCUGCCUCAGCCUCCCAAGUAGCUGGGAUUACAGGCAACCACCACCACGCCCAGCUAAUUUUUUUGGGGGGUCUUUUUAGUAGAGAAAGGGUUUCACCAUGUUGGCCAGGCUAGUCUUGAACUUCUGACCUUAGGUGAUCCACCCACCUCGUCCUCCCAAAGUGCUGGGAUUACAGGCGUGAGCCAGCACACUUUUGAUUACAACUGUCAUAAGAUCUUGUAACCAUUGAGAAUAACUCAUGUGGUUUAUCAAAAACACCUUAUUAUUCCAUUAAACCUACUGAAUAGAACAAAAAUGAUCAUAAAGAUAUUUCAAAGAAUAUGUUCCAAUUUAAUUGGCUCAAAAUAUUCACGUAUAUAAUCAUUAUUACCAAAUGAGGGAUUGGCAUCAAAAUGUGGAUGAUCAAAAAUAAUUUGUUAAACAGAUUAUUCUAUGUUGUGUAUAGUGAUAGAAUAAUUCUUUAAUUAUUUUUCCCGAAUGAAGUCUGAGAUCUUUAGCCCAAGAAGGAGUAGGUGAGUCUUAGCCUGCUUUCUUGGCUAUUGAAUGCUUCUCGAAAGGAUGCCGAAGAACUUGCUGGAGAAGAUGUACCUGGUAAAUAACGUGGGCAGAUAAAUGUUGAUUAUAAUUACCCAGGACCCUGAUGAAUUUCUACAUUUCUAAAAGGCAAGGUCAAUUUUAAAUGUUUAAAAAUGUUUCUACUUUGGGAAGCAGAAGCAGGCAGAUCACUGGAGGUCAGGAGUUGAAGACCAGCCUGGCAAACAUUGUGAAACCUUGUCUGUAUUAAAAACGCAAAAAUUAGCUGGGCAUGGAGGCGUCUGCCUGGACUCCCAGCUACUUGGGAAUUUGAUGCAGGAGAAUGGCUUGAAACUGAAUGUGGAGGACGCAGUGAGCCGAGAUCACGACACUAUACUCCAGCCUGGGCAACAAAGCUAGAUUGUCUCAUAUCGAACAAACAGCAAUAAAAGUUCAUACAUUUUGUUUUAUGAAAAAUCUCAACUCUACUUCUUACUUAGAAUUGUUAUUAUUGCACAGAAGUUCCUUAAGUAUUAUUUUUAUACUAAACUAAGAGAAGGAAUAUGUACACUGUCACGGAGAGUACACAUAUAUCCCAUCAUUUUAAGAUCCCUUUACUGCAUUAAGAGAAUUCUAAUUUUCUAACAUAUUUAGCAAAAAAAAGAAGGUCAAUGAUUUGCAAUCUUUCCAAAUGAAGGGCAUGAAUUCCAGCUCAUGCCGCUUCCUCACUGAGAAUUUGGCUCUAUGAUAAUAAACUGAGGCACCAACGACACACUUCUUUCAACAAUAAAUCAAAGAUUGAAAUGUU